ACACUAAAUAUUUCACUUCACUCUUUUUGCUUGCAUGGUUUCUGAAGAGAAAGUUUGAUCUAAUUCUUUAUUUCUCUGUGGAUAAGAUGUUUUCUGUGUGUGUUGAUUUUUUUCUUUACCUCUUGCUUCUUUCGAGAUAUCUUAUUGGUCUUAAAGUUAAUAAGGAAAAAACUAAAGUUUUGCUUUUGAUUUAGUUUUCUCUUUGUCUUAUUUUCUGCAGCUUCACUAUCAUUUGCCUAUGUAAAUAUUUUGGUAUUUAUCUUGCUUGGUGUUCUCUGAACUUCCAGGUUUGGUGUUUCUUACUAAAGACAUUCUUUCCUGUUACAGUGUUAUUGAUUUGUACACUCCCCUUCCUCGCCUCCCCUCUUCACUGUUUUUUCCUUCUCUUUACUCUUCCUUUCUUUCCACAGGAUCUCACUCUGUCACCCUGGCUGGAGUGCAGUAGUGGCGUGAUCAUAACUCGCUGCAGUCUUGAACUCCUAGGCUCAAGUGAUUCUCCCUCCUCAGCUUCUCAAGUAGCCAGGACUACAGGUGUGUGCCACCAUGCCUGGCGAUUAAAAAAAAAAUCGUAGAAACAGGGUCUCCAAUGUUGCCCAGGCCGGUCUUAGAAAAAAGGACUUAGCUGGGCAUGGUGGUGGCAUGCACCUGUAGUCCUACCUGCUUGGGAAGCUGUGGCAGGAAGAUUGUUUGUGCCUAGGAGUUCAAGGCUACAGUGCGCUGUGAAUCACCACUGUACUCCAGACUGGGUAACAGUGAGACCCUGUCUCAAAACAUAUAUAUAAAAAAAAAUUCCUGGUGAUAAUUUGAUAAUUCCUGGUAAAAAUUUCUGCCACAUCCGAGUCUGUUUCCGAGGCUUGCUUUGUUUCUUCAGAUUGUAUUUUUUGCCUUUAUAGUGCCUCAUAAUUUUUUUUCAUAGCCAGACAGAAUGUAUCAGGUAAAAGGAACUGAGGUAAAUAGGCCUUUAGUGUGAGGUUUUAUGUUUAUCUGUUUAGAAGUCAGGCUGUGUUUAGUGUUUGUUCUGGCUGUGGUAUCGGAGGCAAAUGUUACGGGAUCUUUAAGGUGUUGCUUUUCUGUCUAGAAACCUCUGUGGCCAGUGGCGCCUUUGCCCGAGUUCUUGUCCUGUGUCCAGGAAGAAUUAUGUAUGCAGACAAGUGGAGGGUGAGCAAGACAAAGAGAAGCUUUACUGAGUGUUAGAACAGCUCAGAGGAGAGCUGCAGAGGGCAGCCCCUCUCUAUAGGCAGGUUGUCUCAUCCAGUGUUCAGCUCUCAGCAGAGAGGAGGCCCUGGAGUGAGUGGCUCCUCUCUGCAGGCAGGUCCCCAUUGACUUCCCAGCUCUCAGCAGAGACGAUAGCUCCUCUCUGCAGCUAGUCAUCUGGCUGUCUCUCUGGCCUCUGCCCUGCUCUGGCUGAUCUCGGGGCUUUUAUGGACCUCAGUGGGGAGGAAGUGUGUCAAUUGGUACAUCGGUGGCCAUGGGUGGGCUGGAAAAGGCACCACAAGCCCCCACUGCAGUCUGCGGGACUGGCAGCCCGGUCCCCAACGUUCAGGCCCUCCCUGGCCUGAAGGUGGGGUCUAUCUGGGGACGUGCCCCCUUCCACCCAGGAGCCUGUCUGCUUCCUGCCACUUUCCAUGGCUCCCAGGCUGCUUGUGCCAAGGGGCACCUGCCUGCCAGCAUGGAGCAGCUCUCCACCUCAGCUUCCUCAGAGGGGGCCUAGGCGGCAGGGCCUGAGCAUGCGCAUAUCCUGUUGGGCUGUGAUGAUAUCCAGGCUUGGCUCCAACCCCACUCUGAGAACCUGCCACAUUGGAGCCGGUGCGGGAAGUGGCAGCGGGAACAGGCAUUUCCGAGCCUGCAAAGGCAAGGGGGGCCUUCCUGAGCCCCCAAGAGCACACGGAGGCCUGGGUCCACAACCCUGACUUGGGUAGCUGCAGCUGUAUGGGGUUGGGGGACAGGGCUCCUGCCUGUUUCCAGUCCCCAAGAGCACAUGGAGGCCUGGGUCUACCACCCAGGCUUGGGUGGCUUGGGCUGCUGCCUGCUCCUGGCUCCCACUGGCACUGUGGAGCAUGCAGCCCUGGCUCCGCCCCCUUUCAGCCUGAGACAGGGGCUCCAGAUCCUUGCUGGACCUGGGCUGGGAUCCGGGGCAGGGGUGACAUCGCCGGGAGCUACCCCAGUUGCCCUGGCGCUUCAGUGGCCCAGGCAGAGCAGAUAACUGUCCGGCCUGGCUGUUGGGAGUGGCAGGCUCAGCAGUCGCCUGAUGUGGGGUGGACCCUGGGGAUGUAGCCCCGGGCAGCCCUGCACAGAGCCUCCUCCUGAGGCCCAGGAACCUGGCACCCUCAGUGGGGUGGGCGCAGUGGCUGUGUCACUGGCUGGUCCCUGAAGUGGGCACCGCUCCCACUUCCUGCCUCAGGCCCCUGAAGCUCAGCCUCAGCUCUGCAUCGGUCUGCUCUCUGCUUGACUGUGCUGCACAGAGGGCGGCGGGCUGUUGAGGGAGGGGGUCUGUCCGCCUCUCCCUGUGCCGUCCAUGUACCAGAAAGCCACCGCCAUCACUAUUAGAGGCUAAAAUUUCUUCUACUGUCCUUGCUUUUAUCUGCCCUGUUGUCUUUGGGUUUUUGUAAAGAAUCCUUAAAUGGGGUCUGAGGCUUGCAGGUUUUUAAGUUGUAAUCCUGUGUUGUACAAGAGCUGUACUGAUGUGGUGGUAAGGGUAGAGGGAUGAGGGGGAAAGUUCUAUAGUCCUGUAAUUAGAUCUCAGGACUAUAGAACUUUCCCCCUCAUCCCUCUGCCCUCUACCAACUGUGAGCCUGAGUUGAGUAACUGUCUCUUUUUCUCGGUCAAAGGAUAGAUGGGGCUGGAGUUGGGUAUUUCCCUUCCCUCCGGUUGGUUAGGCACUGUAAAACCGUAGUAGGUUAGGCAAUCUAAAAGCCAGUUGGUUAGGUUCUGGUAAAAUAGUUUCCUUUUCUGGAAUACCUUUUAAGAGAAAUAAAGUUCCUGGCGUAUUUCAAAAUGGUUUUUCUUCUUCCCCUGCUGCAAGCAGGAGGGGUUUUUUUUCAGAUCUUUACCAUGAGAACCUGGUAGGGCUCCUGGAGGUAAAACUCAGGAAAGUAUGGGGACCCCUGUAAGACUGGUCCCCUUACAGUUUUUAACUCUCAAGCUAGUCCACAAUUACUGUUUCAAGUGUUCCUACUGAUGCUGGCUUCAGUUGAGAGCUUGUAUUCCUGGACUUCUGCUUCCUGCACACUGUGAUUCUCUAUCUGCCUGUCUUGUCUCUCCAGGUUUUAGAGCAGCAGUUUGCCCUCUGACCUCAAUUCUCUGAUGGCUCUAAGAAGAGUUGGAUUAUCAGUUUUUUUUUUUUUACCCCCAGCUUUUUUUCUUGUCGUGAGGUUGGGAGUGAUGAAUUACAAGCUCUUUACAACUGUACUUAAGGUUAUUUUUUGACCAUUUUUGAUGCUUUUGUAACUAGUCAAAAGACUUAUUACAGUAUCCUUUAUCUCAUUUGGCAGUAUUGUUCAUUAAGAAUUUUAUCUCUUUCUGACAUCAGGUCUGCACAUUUUGGGGAUAAUAUAUUCUAAUUUGCAAGAAAGAUUAAAAAACUUCUCCAGAGGGAAGUUGAUCAUAGGACUGAUUCUUAUUAUUGAUGAAUUGACUGCCUUGUCUUGUUUUGUGUUGCUAUGUAGGAAUACCUGAGGCUAGGUAAUUUAUAAAGAGUUUGAUUUACCGCACAGUUCUGCAGGCUGUACAAGAAGUAUGGCACCAGGAUCGGCUUGUAGUGAGGGCCUUAGGCUACUUCCACUGAUAGCAGAAGGCAAAGAGGUGCCAGCUUGUGCACAAAAUGAGAGAGGAGAAAAGGGUGGGAGGAGGGGCCCUGGCUCUUUUUAACAACCAGCUCUUGGGGGAACAAAUAGAGUGAGACCUCAAGCAUGCCUGAGGAAGAGCAUUAAUUUAUUCUUGAGGGUUCUGACCCCUCCCCACCAUGCCCAACAACAUCUCCCAUUAGGCCCCACCCCCAACAUUGAGAUCAAAUUUCAACAGGAGGGACAAUCAUCUAAGUGAUAGCAUAGACUCAGGCUAUUUACUAUUCUGUUUUCAAGUAUAGAUUGAGGGCAACAGCAGCCUUUGUUUUCUAUGUUGAUGGCCAAAGGUUUAUUUUUAUAUUCUUAUACUGUAAAAAAAAAAACAACUUUAUUUUUAUAGCCUUUUUGGGUGUAGGGUCAUGUCAGGCUUUACUAAUUGCACUUCUGAUAAGUAUACUGAUGAUGCUGAGGAUGGUUAUUAAAGCCCUAUGCUGAUACUUUGGAUUUAUGGAACCAAUUAAUUUGAUGACUCAUUUACAUUGAAUUUCUUAAUUAGUAGAUUGCCCACUAAUUAUUUUUAUGAGCACAGAAUAAGGUAAUGUUUAUUCUUAUUUUUUUUGUGAUAUGGUAAAAAACUUAGUUCAUAUAAUGAAUUUAGUGCUCAAAUAUCUUAGUAGAAAUUGAAGUAGAAAAAGACAUUGUUGUAAAUUAAAUGUAAGAUAUAAUUUUAUUUUCUUUAGAAAACUUUACAUUGAAAAGAUCACAUUAUAGAUAAUUUAGACAACUUAUUUAUAACUUUUAUUUAUUAUUAUUAUUGAAUGUAAAAGAAUUACAUGCAGUCCCAUGAUCUUAACAUAACUGUGGUUACCAUGUUGGUAUAUGUGCCUUUUAGUCCUUUUUCAUACACAAUUUUUUUUACAAAGUUAUAAUAAUAAUUUCUUUUCAAAUUUGUGCCUUAUUUCAGUUAACAGUGUAAAUGUUUCCCAUUUCUAACAAUGUUUUCUCAUUGAGUGAGGUACUGUUAGGUUGGUCAGACUGAUAGUUUAUUGUACGUAUUGCUGUAAUAUCUUUGUACAUUUAGCUUUUCCAUGUUUGUACCAUAUCUUUGGGUUUUCAGAAGUCUGUCUCUCUCUCUGUUUCUCUUUUUGUCUGUCUUUUCUAUCUCUCACCUUCAUUUGGGGAGCAUUUUGUGUUCUCUUUCACAGGACUAAUUAAGUUUUAUUGGAUCUUGAAAAACGGGAUUAGAAAUUUUUUCUUACUUAUAUAAUUAGAAAACAAUGCUUUUGGACUUACAUUGCCACGGCAGUUUACACAGUUUUAUUCCCAAAAAUUGUAGUUUUGUGACUAGGUGAUAAAAAUGAUCUCCUAUAUGUGCCAAACUUGGUAUUCUAGACACUCAUACUUAGGAUGUAAAUUGACUGUAGUCCAAUAAUUUAAUAUGUUGUGUUUAAUUCUUGUAAUAUUUUACUCACAAAUUGAACUUUUCCUUACCAAUUUAAUGUUUGUAGGCUUAAUUUGGCAUCUUUGUCAGGAUUAUUAGACUUCUCUGCAUUCUUCUGACUUCUCCCUAAACUAAUGUUUAGAACUGAAUUGGGUCCAGCAAUUUAAGUGGAAAAUCAGUAUGACUAGAGACUUCUAGAAACUUCUGGUGUCACUGAGAUGGUGAAUUUGAUGAUUCUGACCCUACUUGCUCAUCUGUAAAAGCUAUUAGAGGAUUGUUUUAAGCAUUUCUAUUCUAUACAGGUAUAUGUACACCAUGUAAUACCACUCAGCCAUAAAGAAGAAUGAAAUAACAUUUUUGCAGCAAUUUGGGUGGAGCUGUAGGCCAUUAUUCUAAGUGAAGUAACUCAGGAAUACAAAACUGAAUACCAUAUGUUCUCACAAGCGGGAGCUAAGUCAUGGGUACGCAAAGGCAUACAGAAUAGUAAAAUAGACUUUGGAGACUGAGACGCGGGGAGAAUAGGAAGAAGAUAAGGGAUAAAAAACGAUAUAUUGGGUACAAUGUAUGCUACUUUGGUGAUGGGUGUAGUAAAAUCUCAGACUUCACCACUAUACAUUUCAUCCAUGUAACCCAAAACCACUUGUACUCCAAAAGCUAUUGAAAUAAAAAAGAUAUUUAAAAAAAAAGAGGCCAGGCAGGUUGGUUCACGCCUGUAAUCCCAGCACUUUGGGAGGCUGAGGCGGGCGGAUCACUUGAGGUCAGGAGUUCGGGACCAGCCUGACCAACAUGGUGAAAACCUGUCUCUACUGAAAAAAAAAAAAAAAAGCCAGGCGUGCUGGCUCCCACCUGUAAUCCCAGCUACUCAUGGGGCUGGGCGAAUCGCUUGAACCUGGGAGGCAGAGGUUGCAGUGAGCCGAGAUUGUGCCACUGCACUCUAAGAGCAAAACUCUGUCUCAAAAAUAAAUAAAUAAAUAAAAAAUUAAAAAAGAUCUUCUGUUGUACCUAAUCUUCUAGCCUUAUUAUUUCUUAGAGAUUUUAUAAAUCCAUGUGGCUUUUUUACUCUUGUCAUCUUCAAGUUAUUUGCCAAGAUUGAAAAAUAACCAUCUUUCUCCUAAUACCUUGGUGAGCCUGAGAGAAGAAAAUACUACACAGUUCAUUUUAUUGUAAAAGUAGUGAAAUUUCUCAACUGAUAUUCAUCCUUCAUUUUUGUGGAUUUGUUCAGGGAAGAUAAGAUUUAUUGUUUAUUUUUAUUUUGCUGUAUUGCCAGGCUGGUCUGGAACUUCUGAGCUCAAGCAGUCCUCCUGCCUCGGCCUUCCAAAGUGUUGGGAUUAUAGGUGUGAGCCACCGCACCUGGCUGGAAGACAGGAUUUUUUUGGGAAAGUAAAUAUCACUUGAGAAUAUCUACUAGUAUGGAAUCUAAAGUUAUGCAUACAAGGAUGAUCUCAUAUUUCUUUGUAUCUUGUUCCCAGUCUUUCCCCCAAUCUUGUCUCGCUUUUUCCUCAACAAGCGUAGUUAACAACUACUAUGAAUUUGGAAUACAAAAUGAUAACGACCCUGCCUUUAGGAAACUGACAAUUUAGAAGGUCAACUAGAAAUAUAAGUUAAUAAUUACAGUACAGGAAGUCCCCUGAUUUCCUCUAUAAUAACAUGUCUCCCAAAAUGUGAUUGAAAAUAAAAAUUCCACAUGUCAUAGGCGUAGGAGGUAUUUGGGUGUUUGUAUGGAGAGUCAUUUCACAGAGCUAAAAUUUAUUAUUAUAAAAUACUCAAUUCUAGUUCCUGGGCAUGUUAUCUCCUUUGGAAUUAGAAAUCUUAGUUGCUGCAUAACAUUAAAAGUGUCAGGAUGAUGCCUGUAAUCCCAGCACUUUUGAAGGUAGAGGCAGAGCAUUGCUUGAGGCCAGGAUUUUGAGACCAGCCUGGGCAACAUAGUGAGACCCUGUCUCUACCAAAAAAUUUAAAAAAAUUAGCCAAGCAUGGUGGUGUGUGCAUGUAGUCCUAGGUACUUAGGAGGCUGAGGCAGAGGAUCGCUUGAGCUCAGGUAUUUGAGGCUGCAGUGAGGCUGCAGUGAGGCUGAGCUCUACCAUAUAGAGCUCAGGCUCUAUAUGGUAGAGCCACUGCAAUCCAGCCUCCGCAACAGAGUGAGACCUUGUCUUGGGGGGCAAAAAGUGUAAGGAUGGGAUUUCUAGGCAUAUUUGGGGCUGAGGAAAUCAGUCUUGGGCCCAACCUCCUUGUAGGGGGUGAGGUGGCAACCUCUGGAAUUUGAGGCCUGCUACUGGGAUUGUAGGUAUAGGAAGUUGAGAGGGAAAGGGUCUUUCUCACCCUGCUGUGGUAGUAAGAGCUUGGUGCUUAAUGGGUGCCUUUUAGUUGUUUGAUCACCUAGGAUUUCUGCUUAGAACCCAGCAAUACUUGUAGGCCUGCACAGUCCCAAGAGAGAAAUCAGAGACUUGGUGAUAAGUCAAGGGUAAGAGAUGAGAUAAGAGAGCACCUACACUAUAGGAUAUUAGAACUACAACUCCAAUUACUCCUUCACUCUCAUCUUUUUCCCUCUCCCAGCUGCCAAGUAUAUGUGACUAGUGGUUUGUCCAGAGCAGGACUGGAGGAUGGGGUAGGAAGAAUUAUUAUUUUUUCAUCAUAGAUCAGGAUAGUGUCAUGUCCCCCUAAACUUCAGGGAGGCCUGGCUUCAUACCUCUUCUUCCAAUUUCCUAGCAUUGUGCAAUGACAAAGCUUCAUGCAGUAACUCAAAAUCAUUGUUAAUAAGGUGAUAUCUAAAAGAUUGAAUUUGAUGUUCUGAAGUUAGUGUGAGGAUGUCAGUCUGUUAAUGUGUGAAAUGUUUUGAGCUGUGUGAAACUCAAUUUUGCUUAGUGUGUUAAGUACAACUGAAGUAGGUGUAAAAGUCAGUAGUAGCACACAGAAAGGAGUAAUGAAUUGUGUCUAGAGGGUCAGGAAAGGUCUCACAAAGGAGAGGAUCCUUGAAUUCUUUGUUCAAGUGGUAGAGUUAAAGAAGUAGAUUUUUUUUUUUUUUUUUUUUUUUUUUUUUUUUUUGGCGACAGGGUUUUGCUGUAGGUCUCCCAGGCUGGAGUACAGUGGCGCUAUCAUAGCUCACUGCAAUCUCUAAACUUCUGGGCUCAAGCAUAGAAAUAGAUCUGAUAGUGGAAGUCUCUGCCCAGUAAUACUGAGAUCUUGGAACCUUACUCAUUUCAGAAAUGGCUCUGGUCUGAAUACAUUAUAUGGGACUAAGCUCUUCUAAAUAUCUUUAUCCCUUAAUUCUUUAUGCAUAAACUUCAGCAACUUCUAAGCUACCAUUAGGAAAUUUUCACUGUAAAUUAUAUACUGGAUGAUUGAAUUUUUAGAAUUAGAUUUAUUCCAAAUGUAAGUCAACCUAAAUGUAAAGUUUUUCUCUACUUAAAUAUAAGCUUUUUUGGCACUCUUGAAGAUUCUGAGUAUUUCUGUGGACAGUUAUGGCCAUCAGGGUGUUUGUUUGAAUUCUGGAAUUGCCCUAGAGAGCACAUAAGCUGUGGAGUAAAGCAGGUGUGUGGUCUGACUCCUGACUUGGUCACUUAAGAUCUGUGCAACCUUGAAUAGUAACUUCGAUGCUAAUUUUCCACAUCUGUAAAAUAUGGAUAAAAAAUGCAGAGUCUUUAGCACAGUUCCUGGCAUGAAGUAAUGGCUCAAUAAAUGUUAAUUAUUACUAUUGUUAACUAAAUAAGAGUUCCCUAGGUCUCUGACUUCAAACAUAUAGUUGUUGGAGACUAUGAAUACCUUGGGGCCACCUUGAGCUAAGACUAGAUGCUCAGGAGCACCUUUUUGAUUAGUCAUUUAUUCAUUGAGCAUAUAUUUUUGCAUUGUUUAAACUUUAGCAAAAUACCUAAGUCAGUCAAUUCUAUUUUUAUACAGAUAUUUCUAUAUAGAGGAGAUUUCCUAUAGGAUGACCUGUUCUGGGUGUGUCUAUCUGACCUGCAGCUAAUCAAGUGACUACAGCUUUGCUAAUUUUUUUUUUGAAAAACCCUAAUAUUGUUAAACAGUAGUACAGAGGAAAUAAGCUGUUGGUCAGCUUCUAAAUUCUGGCACGGGUUAGAUUUGCCUAAGAGCAAAUCAUAUAGCAAGAGUUGAUGAGAGAACUUUUCUCAUAUCUUCUAGCCUGGGUAAGUUUGUCUCAUUUGGUGUCAAGUCAGAGGAAUCUGAACUAUAGAACCAAAUUGUAGGGAAAGAUGACUAAGGGUUUGUGAUGUCUUUUUUUUUUUUUACCCCCCUCAAAGGAGUUCUAGGUGUAAAAAGCAUCAUGGUUUAAACGUUACGAGGCAUCAGUGAAGGCAGCAGAAAAGUCAGAAACUAAUAUAGCCAAGUCUAGAUUGUAUCUGUUAUAAACUCUUUAAUCAGAAGAUUCUAGCUUCUAGAACCAGGUCUGUAAAAUGUUGAGAGCCCUCUAAGUAAACUCCAUUAUAGUCAUUUAAUUGAUUUUUCUUUGUCUUUCUUCUUGGACAUACUCUUCUUUAAAGAGAGCGUUCCCCCCUCUACCCCAGAUAGUAUCUAUCUUUGAGGUUUUGAGAACAAUAGUAUUCUUGUUCUUUAGGUUCUGAGUUGCUGACUUGAGGGAAUUUGAUACACAGGAGUCCCCAAGGCCCCCCAGUGGAUACCUGAAACCAUGGAUAGUACUGAACCCUAUAUAUACAGGUCAGGCAUCCCAAAUCUGAAAUCCAAAACGUUCCAAAAUCUGAAACCGACGUGACACUCUGAAGAAAUGCUCACUGGAGCAUUUUGGAUUUGUGGAUUUGAGAUGCUCAACUGGUAAGUAUAACACAAAUAUCCCCAAUAGGAAAAACUCCCUAUUCCCAUUAGUUUUUACUUGAUAUUCUGAAUUCUUAAGUGUGAUUUUUUUUUCUAAUUUGGGGAUAGCUCCUAUUUUUGUGAGAGAAAUUAAUGGGAAAUUUUGAGAUGGUAACUAGAAAUUGUCUUUGCAGUGUUAAAUUUUUAGUUGGGAGGCUACUAGGCUGGGUGGCUCUAGCUGUUUAAGUUCCUGUCUAAGCAAACCAAAGCCCAACUUAGAAAGUAAAAGGAAACUAGAUAUUUUGCCAACUAGAAACCACCUAAGUAAUCUCUAACUAGUGUCUUUCCACUCUGACCAAUGAGAUAUGUUUUCUUUGUCUUCCGUGUUCAGCCUAUAAAGCUUACAGCCCACACUGCUGUGAAUGAAGCUCUUCAAACCUUUUAUGGUUCAGAGUGCUGCCUAAUUGAUGAAUCAUUCUUUGCACAGAUAAACUCUUUUGUCUGUUUUUGCUUUAAACAACAAAGGAACAUAAAUUCUGUUAAUUGAUUGUAUGAAUAUAACAGUGAAAAUUCCCUGUUAGGCUUUGGUUAUCAGUAUUUUAGGAAUACUUUUUAAAACAUCCCCUUUAGCUUUUAAUGUGUUUUGGUUAGACAAGAUGAUGUAUGUGUCAGUAUAAUGCCAGGCUCACAAAAGUUGCUAACUAAAUGUUAGUUCCUUCAAUACAUACAUUCAUUCCCUGGGACAUGGUUCCAAAAGUAGAUUAUCAUAAGAAUUCUGUGAGAAGCUUUGAAAAAACUACAGAUGUCUAUGGCAUAUAUUAAUACAUGGCGUCUAUAUCCAUACAUGUAUGUAAAUGUAUGCAAACAAUUUAAUCUACUUUUUCCUUAACAUUAACUCCUUCAGAUAGAAUGGUUGGCCCAAAUGAUUUAAUUAUUUUUUAGGUUGUUGAUUCAUAGAAACAAAUCCCCUGCAGAAAGGUUGUACCAAUUUACACGGUUACCUUUCUUCACAUUUUCUCUAACACUGGGUAUUCUUGAGCUUUUAGUAUUUCUCAGUUGGUGGAAAGGAUCUCUUAGUUUGUUGGGAUCUCUUUGAUUAUGAGUGAGAUUCAGCAUUUUCCAUAAUUUACUGAUGUCUGCAUUUCUUCCUCCCUCCUUCCCUUUCUUCUUUCCUUUCUCCUUCUCCUACUUCCACUUUCUCCCGUCCUGUCCUCCCUUUCCCCUGCUCUCCCUCUUUCUUCCCCUUCUAUCCCCCUCCCCUCCUGUUUUUCCUUCUUUGCUUGUUUUUGAUCUCUGUUCUUCCACAUAUGAAGAUUCUAUUUUGACCAGCAAUAAGUUGAAUUAUGGGGCUAGAAGAUAAGGACUAAAAACAAGAAUUGGUGUCCAGAAAGCAUGUAGAGCGCAUGAAGUACAGGACAAUAAAGCUUCCUACACAUAUCACCAGGAGGAUCUCUUUGAAAGAUUCACUGCAGGACUACCAGAGAGAAUAAUUUGUCUGAAGCAUCAUGUGUUGAAACAACAGAAGUCUAUUCACCUGUGCACUAACUAGAAACAGAGUUACAAUGUUUUCAAUUCUUUGAGCUCCAGGACUCCAGGGAAGUGAGUUGAAAAUCUGAAAAUGCGGCCAUGGACUGGUUCCUGGCGUUGGAUUAUGCUCAUUCUUUUUGCCUGGGGGACCUUGCUGUUUUAUAUAGGUGGUCACUUGGUACGAGAUAAUGACCAUCCUGAUCACUCUAGCCGAGAACUGUCCAAGAUUCUGGCAAAGCUUGAACGCUUAAAACAACAGAAUGAAGACUUGAGGCGAAUGGCCGAAUCUCUCCGGAUACCAGAAGGCCCUAUUGAUCAGGGGCCAGCUAUAGGAAGAGUACGCGUUUUAGAAGAGCAGCUUGUUAAGGCCAAAGAACAGAUUGAAAAUUACAAGAAACAGACCAGAAAUGGUCUGGGGAAGGAUCAUGAAAUCCUGAGGAGGAGGAUUGAAAAUGGAGCUAAAGAGCUCUGGUUUUUCCUACAGAGUGAAUUGAAGAAAUUAAAGAACUUAGAAGGAAAUGAACUCCAAAGACAUGCAGAUGAAUUUCUUUUGGAUUUAGGACAUCAUGAAAGGAUUCUGAUGGCAAUUACUGUCUCAUUAGUGAACAAUAAAAGAAAAAUUGUUGUAUUAGCACAACCUACUACUGUGAAGAGGAAAAGAAUUACCCCAUACAAGUCUAUAAUGACGGAUCUAUACUACCUCAGUCAGACAGAUGGAGCAGGUGAUUGGCGGGAAAAAGAGGCCAAAGAUCUGACAGAACUGGUUCAGCGGAGAAUAACAUAUCUUCAGAAUCCCAAGGACUGCAGCAAAGCCAAAAAGCUGGUGUGUAAUAUCAACAAAGGCUGUGGCUAUGGCUGUCAGCUCCAUCAUGUGGUCUACUGCUUCAUGAUUGCAUAUGGCACCCAGCGAACACUCAUCUUGGAAUCUCAGAAUUGGCGCUAUGCUACUGGUGGAUGGGAGACUGUAUUUAGGCCUGUAAGUGAGACAUGCACAGACAGAUCUGGCAUCUCCACUGGACACUGGUCAGGUGAAGUGAAGGACAAAAAUGUUCAAGUGGUCGAGCUUCCCAUUGUAGACAGUCUUCAUCCCCGUCCUCCAUAUUUACCCUUGGCUGUACCAGAAGACCUCGCAGAUCGACUUGUACGAGUGCAUGGUGACCCUGCAGUGUGGUGGGUGUCUCAGUUUGUCAAAUACUUGAUCCGCCCACAGCCUUGGCUAGAAAAAGAAAUAGAAGAAGCCACCAAGAAGCUUGGCUUCAAACAUCCAGUUAUUGGAGUCCAUGUCAGACGCACAGACAAAGUGGGAACAGAAGCUGCCUUCCAUCCCAUUGAAGAGUACAUGGUGCAUGUUGAAGAACAUUUUCAGCUUCUUGCACGCAGAAUGCAAGUGGACAAAAAAAGAGUGUAUUUGGCCACAGAUGACCCUUCUUUAUUAAAGGAGGCAAAAACAAAGUACCCCAAUUAUGAAUUUAUUAGUGAUAACUCUAUUUCCUGGUCAGCUGGACUGCACAAUCGAUACACAGAAAAUUCACUUCGUGGAGUGAUCCUGGAUAUACAUUUUCUCUCUCAGGCAGACUUCCUAGUGUGUACUUUUUCAUCCCAGGUCUGUCGAGUUGCUUAUGAAAUUAUGCAAACACUACAUCCUGAUGCCUCUGCAAACUUCCAUUCUUUAGAUGACAUCUACUAUUUUGGGGGCCAGAAUGCCCACAAUCAAAUUGCCAUUUAUGCUCACCAACCCCGAACUGCAGAUGAAAUUCCCAUGGAACCUGGAGAUAUCAUUGGUGUGGCUGGAAAUCAUUGGGAUGGCUAUUCUAAAGGUGUCAACAGGAAAUUGGGAAGGACGGGCCUAUAUCCCUCCUACAAAGUUCGAGAGAAGAUAGAAACGGUCAAGUACCCCACAUAUCCUGAGGCUGAGAAAUAAAGCUCAGAUGGAAGAGAUAAACGACCAAACUCAGUUCGACCAAACUCAGUUCAAACCAUUUCAGCCAAACUGUAGAUGAAGAGGGCUCUGAUCUAACAAAAUAAGGUUAUAUGAGUAGAUACUCUCAGCACCAAGAGCAGCUGGGAACUGACAUAGGCUUCAAUUGGUGGAAUUCCUCUUUAACAAGGGCUGCAAUGCCCUCAUACCCAUGCACAGUACAAUAAUGUACUCACAUAUAACAUGCAAACAGGUUGUUUUCUACUUUGCCCCUUUCAGUAUGUCCCCAUAAGACAAACACUGCCAUAUUGUGUAAUUUAAGUGACACAGACAUUUUGUGUGAGACUUAAAACAUGGUGCCUAUAUCUGAGAGACCUGUGUGAACUAUUGAGAAGAUCGGAACAGCUCCUUACUCUGAGGAAGUUGAUUCUUAUUUGAUGGUGGUAUUGUGACCACUGAAUUCACUCCAGUCAACAGAUUCAGAAUGAGAAUGGACGUUUGGUUUUUUUUUGUUUUUGUUUUUGUUUUUUCCUUUAUAAGGUUGUCUGUUUUUUUUUUUUUAAAUAAUUGCAUCAGUUCAUUGACCUCAUCAUUAAUAAGUGAAGAAUACAUCAGAAAAUAAAAUAUUCACUCUCCAUUAGAAAAUUUUGUAAAACAAUGCCAUGAACAAAUUCUUUAGUACUCAAUGUUUCUGGACAUUCUCUUUGAUAACAAAAAAUAAAUUUUAAAAAGGAAUUUUGUAAAGUUUCUAGAAUUUUAUAUCAUUGGAUGAUAUGUUGAUCAGCCUUAUGUGGAAGAACUGUGAUAAAAAGAGGAGCUUUUUAGUUUUUCAGCUUAUUUACUUUGUUUUUUUUCCUGUUUCUGAUAUAGUAACUAAUUCUUAACUCAGAGACAUUGGUCCAUUUUAAUACUGAAAACCAAUUUUCAUUGGUACACAUUACAAAAUUGCUAAGAACACUGUUUGGGAGCUUUCAUUCUCAUAUUUUGGACAUUGUUUUAAUUGAGUGAAAUAAUCAUAACUCCUUGCUCCCAGAGAAGCUAUCACCUCCAUUUCUAAAACCAUUUCAGGUUUGUUUGGUAGUCUUUCUUAAUGUAUUUAUUAUCGCUUUUUGUGAGUAGGGUCCUGUUUUAUCCAGGAACCAAUUUCUGCCCUAGCCUAUCAUGCCCUGCUUUUGAGAGUACCAGGUAUCUUUGGGAUUGGGAAGCUGGCUGUUUCAGAAGUAUAUGUCUCAUAGUGUGCAGAACUUGGUGACCAAGUGAGAAGCGGGACCAAUGGGAGACUCACAAUGGACUGAGUCUUGGGAUUAUCUUUUCCAAAUUCUUCCAUGUUAGAAUCACUUCAGAAAAUAAGACUUUGAUGCUUUGUCUCUGAGCAUCAUUUUUCUCCUCAUAAAAACACUUCCUUAUUGUAUGUAGCCUGCCUCCUACAGAGGCCUGGUAGGUGUUACUGCAUUCUAAAAGAAAAAUGUCAUCUCUGUAGGAGCGACUAUCAGGCCUAGUGUGAAAUAUUAGGGAUCCUAGGCAGAAGAGCUAUUAGUCCUGGCCUUCAUAUCUUCACCAAAUGAAAAUACUGUAUAUAAAAUUUCACCACCAAACUUAACUAAAUUCUUUUUCUCAAGUCAAGCCUCCCAAAGAAAAAAGAAAUUAACUUCCUACAGUGUCAGCAAGCAAUUUUCCAUUUAGUUUUGGUACAAAUAAAAGUCAUUUGAAACAA